GCGACGCCCCGCCUCUGGCUCGGGUGCGGGAGCGGGGCCUGCCCGGACUGCGACGCCGCCACAGCUUGGGGCCAGUUCGCCCAGUCAGGGGGAUGGCUCGGUCGGCCUCGGGGGUCGACGAUCCCCCGGGUAGGCGACGUGCCCUGUCCAGGCCUCACUUCCCGCGUCCGCAAAACGGGGUGGACAACGCAGCCUAAGGCAGAGCCGCGCCAAGGUCCCUCGCUGUCGCCGGGCUCUGGCGGCCUGACCGGGCCUGGGGUCCGAGCGUGCCCCCGGGCCUGGGGGGGUCGCCGCGAUGGACUCGCUGGCAGCGCCCCAGGACCGCCUGGUGGAGCAGCUGCUGUCGCCGCGGACCCAGGCCCAGAGGCGGCUCAAGGACAUUGACAAGCAGUACGUGGGCUUCGCCACACUGCCCAACCAGGUGCACCGCAAGUCGGUGAAGAAAGGCUUUGACUUCACACUCAUGGUGGCUGGUGAGUCAGGCCUGGGGAAGUCCACACUGGUCCACAGCCUCUUCCUGACAGACUUGUACAAGGACCGGAAGCUGCUCAGUGCUGAGGAGCGCAUCAGCCAGACGGUAGAGAUUCUAAAACACACGGUGGACAUUGAGGAGAAGGGAGUCAAGCUGAAGCUCACCAUCGUGGACACGCCGGGAUUCGGGGACGCUGUCAACAACACCGAGUGCUGGAAGCCCAUCACCGACUAUGUGGACCAGCAGUUUGAGCAGUACUUCCGUGAUGAGAGCGGCCUCAACCGAAAGAACAUCCAAGACAACCGAGUGCACUGCUGCCUAUACUUCAUCUCCCCCUUCGGGCAUGGGCUGCGGCCAGUGGAUGUGGGUUUCAUGAAGGCAUUGCAUGAGAAGGUCAACAUCGUGCCUCUCAUCGCCAAAGCUGACUGUCUUGUCCCCAGUGAGAUCCGGAAGCUGAAGGAGCGGAUCCGGGAGGAGAUUGACAAGUUUGGGAUCCAUGUAUACCAGUUCCCUGAGUGUGACUCGGACGAGGAUGAGGACUUCAAGCAGCAGGACCGGGAACUGAAGGAGAGCGCGCCCUUCGCCGUUAUAGGCAGCAACACGGUGGUGGAGGCCAAGGGGCAGCGGGUCCGGGGCCGACUGUACCCCUGGGGGAUCGUGGAGGGCGCAUUGCGACUUCGUGAAGCUGCGCAACAUGCUCAUCCGCACGCAUAUGCACGACCUCAAGGACGUGACGUGCGACGUGCACUACGAGAACUACCGCGCGCACUGCAUCCAGCAGAUGACCAGCAAACUGACCCAGGACAGCCGCAUGGAGAGCCCCAUCCCGAUCCUGCCGCUGCCCACCCCGGACGCCGAGACUGAGAAGCUUAUCAGGAUGAAGGAUGAGGAACUGAGGCGCAUGCAGGAGAUGCUGCAGAGGAUGAAGCAGCAGAUGCAGGACCAGUGACGCUCGCCGCGGACACACCGUCCGUCUCCGGGACGCCCUCGCACCCCUGGACACCAGACCGGACUGUUCCCGACCCGGAGACGCGGGGCCACAGCCCCCAGCUGACCCUAAUUUAUUCUCAGCACCACCCCCUCCCAGGUCAUUGUGUCUGUUUCCGAGGGGCCUGGACCGUAGCCCCCGCCCAGCUGGCCCUCUCUGACCUUGGGGGAUCAGGAGCGAAGUUGGGCGGGACUUCAGAGAUCCGCCUCCCUUGCCCUUCCCCCGCCCCCGGACGGUCACAGCACCCAAACCGCAGGCCCUGCUCUGGCAGGCAGGCAAAGCUAGGCAGAAGAGGAUUCCCAGGAUCCUGGGUCUGUUCCCUGCCCCAGUGCUGCAGAACGGACUUGGGAGCCCUCCUUUGCCUGCUCCCGCGGGUCACCCAGCGAGUGCUGAGACCCCAUUUUCUGUCGAGGCGGGCCGAGUCUUCCCUUAUCCCCAGACGCCUAGCGGGCAGGGUUGGGCUGAAUCAAAUGGGAGCCCUCCAGACAUAAGGAGGCCAGAGGCUGCAAGGAGCGGGGUCGUGACCGCUUACACCCCUUCUCCACAGCCCGGCCCGACCUGGAGGGCCCCCGGGGCACUGGGCGGUGAGCCACCUCCUGGCAACUCUCGGUGCCGUCCCCUGCCCUCGCUCGAGGCCUCUUCUCCCCAGCACCGCUGUGGUGUGCCGGGAUCCUGAGCCUAGGCCUCCCGAUGUUCCCACCCGCAUGAUCCCUUCCCGCCACACGAUGCUCCGUUUUCUUCCGUUGUGAAUGCCGCGUCCUGUCCUGGUGACAGGAGAACAAUGUUGGUGAACGUC